GCUGAGACUAGAUAUUCAAAUAUUCCAAAAGCCAGAGUGUAUGCAAGUUCACUUUCAUCUCACUUGUCAUAGGAAUUUAAACAUUAAGCCUCAAAGUAUGGCACCCUAUAUGUCUUUUCAAAAACAACAACAAACAACCACAUUGUGACUACUAGAUGAGGUAAAAUUUGUAAUAACAGAAUCAAAAAAGUCAACCCUAACUUUUCAGCGCUUGAACUCCCAAUCACCCCCACUAAAGGCUUCUUCGUUAACCUUGAAUCAUAAGAAUCACUGAUCAUCGAGUAAUUUCAAAUAGGAAUGUCGUCAAAGAAGUAGAAUUCGGAAUGUGCACCGUUACAUGUGGUAUUGGUGUUAGAGAAGUUAUAUUAACAAAUGGAUGCCCUGGUGGUGAAUCCAAGUGUGUUGUACGGGUAGAAGAAUGCCGUGGACCAACAGAUUGUGGCUGGGGUAAACCAAUUUCAGAAAGUCUUGAAAGUGUUAGAUUGGCAUGUAUUCACACAUCUCCCUUAAAUCGUUUCAAAUAUAUGUGGAAACUUCUAAGACAAGACCAACAAUCCAUUAUACUUGUAAAUGAUUCAGCAAUCCUAGAAGUACGCAAGGAAAGUCACCCCUUGGCUUUCGAGUGUGACACACUGGAUAAUAAUGAAAUAGUAGCAACUAUUAAAUUCACAGUCUAUACGAGCAGUGAAUUGCAGAUGAGAAGAUCAAGCCUACCAGCCACUGAUGCAGCCCUAAUUUUUGUGCUGACCAUAGGAGUCAUUAUCUGUGUAUUUAUAAUUUUCUUAUUGAUCUUCAUAAUCAUAAAUUGGGCAGCAGUCAAGGCUUUCUGGGGGGCAAAAGCCUCUACACCUGAGGUACAAUCCGAGCAGAGUUCUGUGAGAUACAAAGAUUCAACUUCUCUUGACCAAUUACCAACAGAAAUGCCUGGUGAAGAUGAUGCUUUAAGUGAAUGGAAUGAAUGAUGUUUGAAUGAUAUAUAACAAACCAAAGGAUAUUACAGAAUAUUAGAUUCAUUAUUACAAAAAUAAAAUACACAUUGAAAUACUUUAAUAAUGUUGCGAUGGAUUGCCACAGUGUGAAGGAAAUGCAGUGUGGGGAUAGGACUAUUUUAUCAGUGCAUUUUUCCAGUACAGUUAUCAAAUAUUACUUUUAAUUUGUUCUCAACACUUAUUUCAGGUAAUAGCUUGGGGAUAUUUAUCUAAAGGUACCCCCAACAAAUCUUCUAAGUGCAUUUUUGAUCACUUUGAUAACUUCUUAGGUGAUUUGCCUGUUUUGUCUUAAAUAAGAACAAUGUAAUAUAGAAAUGCUUUACAUAUUAGACUUUCUCUCCCCUGGAAGCACUGGGUUGAACUUGCUAAAGUAAAUCAUACUUUAGAAUCUCUUCAGGGAAUGUGACAUACAAAGUUUGUAAGACAUGAAGUAAUAACGAUAAUGAUAACAAUAAAUGCUUACUUAGUGACUACUA